GAAAAGCAUUCUAGAUGUGGGAGUGGUCCAAGGAUGUGGCAGGCUGCUUUGGGGAUACUGAGCUCCUGCCACAGAGGCAUGGCACAGCCCUGAGCAUCUGCCUGUCAGGGGCAUUGCCAGGGCAACUCCCGCCCUGGAGAAACAAUCGGGUUCCUUCCAGUCCUGAUAUUUGGGGCUAUUCAUUUCUGCUCCCACAGCCAAGUCCUGUAGCUGAGUCAGACUCCUGUGGGCCCCUACCAUUCCUCAAACAGUCCUGGGAUUUCUUAUAUCCAUUUUUUCAGAUGAGAACAUGGAACACUCAGAGGGGUGAAUUGAUUGUCCCUAACCAUGUUCAGGGGGACUUGAACCCAGGGCCUCUGACUGCUAAUAUGUUUCUCUGUCCACCUCUCAAGACUCCAUAGCACAGAGCCUUAUACAGAACAGCCACUGGUGGGUGCCACUGACUGGCUUGCUGCCUCUGUAGCACCAUCAUGUGAAAAUGAUGCCCUGGCAUUUCUGGAACACUACUGGGAGAAACAGGAGGCCGUUUCAGCUCAGAGGGUGAGAGCCUGUGCUCAUGUUGCAGGGAGCGGUCUGCAAGACAGCAUCAAGGGGAGGGGAACCCAGACAGGGGCACCAUCACGAUACACAGAUGCCCAGAGGAUGCAAGGACGGUGGGUGUCCAAACGUCCAGGAGGAAGGAAAGAACUCUUUGAGGUCAGAACUUCCUGCUACUACCUGAGUGACCUUGGCAACUUGUUCAGCCUCUCUGAGCCGUAGUCUUAUUAUUUUAAAAACUGAAAUAAUAAUUCCUUCAUGGAUUAUGGGAAGAGUAAGUAAGAUUUUGUGUGUGUGUGUGUGUGUGUGUGUGUGUGUGUGUGUGUGGUGUGUGUGAACUUCUCAGUAUUGAAUAAAUGGUAUCUGUUGCCUUAACGUUGCUAUUCCCACCUGUUGAUGGAGGACGGACAUGAGACCAACAGGGGAAAGUGGGCCCUUGAGUCACAGGACACAGGGUGCUGGAAGCAGUGAGGGCAUAGGGCUGGCUGGGGAAAAAAGCAGGGUGGGAAAGGAUGCCCCGGUAGCCAGGGGCCCUAGCCCUGCCCACCGCUGCUGACCUCACUGAGAGCUUCCACUUCUUCCUUUUAGGCGCAUUUUCCUGGUACCUCACCAAGCUUGAGGUAGGCCAGGCCCAGGCAUAUCCCACGGUCUGUCUAAACAUGUGUUCUCGUGCUGUGUGACCUUGGACAGGCCCCUGCCCCUCUUUGAGCUUUUCUGUAAAGUAAGCAAUUUCACUUGCUGUGUAAGCACCACCUUGCCUUCUCCCUAGGCACCAGCACCCUGCUGCUGAAAGGAUGGAGGCUCAGGGGGACUGGACUUACAUAGGAGGGCCUGGGACUGGUAACAGGUAAUAAAAGGCCACACAGUUCAUUCAUUUGUUCACACGACAUUUAUUGAGUGCAUCAUAUGUGCUGGGGCUGGAGAUAGACUAAUGAACAAAACAAACAUUCCUGCCCUCAUGGAAGGAGGGUCUUACCUUCCUGUGGAAGGUGAUGUGAUAAACAAUAAACAUGAUAAGUGAGGAACUAACAUAGUGUGUUAGAAGGUGGUCAGUGCUAUGUGCUGUGGAGAGUAUGGCAGAGUGUGGAGGUGGGAGUGCCUGGGAGGGGGUUAACAUUAAAGUCAAGGGUCUGAGUGGACCUUAUUGAGAAAGUGAGGGCAAGUGGGGCAGAUUUGUUUUUCGCAGAUUCAUGCAGAAGGUGCCAGCCACAGGUGUUCCUCUCCUGUGAGAAUUUACCCCAGUGUCUCUGGUCUGCGUCCUAUAUUGGAUGCAACUGUAUCGGAUUCCACUCUUGUUUCCCCAGAAUCCAGUGCAGGGUUCAGCCCGAAUACGUGCUCAGAACUGUGUAUCUAAGGAUUACUCCACACUGGCCUGGACCUGAGAUAGGGCAGCCUGAUUGCCCUUGUUCUCUCAAGUGGGAAAUCCUUCCCGGCACCGCCCGUCUUCAGAGGGAGUAUCAGCCCAUCCAGGCCCAGACCCCACAAGGCCAUACCAAGGGGCGACAGUCCUUGCUGUGUUCAUUGCCGUGUCCACACCAGGCCCCAAAUUCCAUCUGCCGCCAAAUUCCAGGGCUGGAAAUAAUGAGGCAAAUUGUCCCUCACCGCUGAUUAACUUUCAAGUUGCUCUGCUAAACUGGGUGCAGUUGAAGUUUUAGCAAGCCUCCUGGGGACCUCAGGCGGCUUCGGUUUCAGCCUUGUAAAGAGCUGUUAAAGAUCCAAUCAAAAUAAAUAAAAUCAGAUCCAGGAAAGCGAUGUGUUGGUGACUGCAGACCAAACACUCAGGAUAUUCAAGCGCCCCGCUUUUCCAGGGGGUUCCUUACACUCCACUGGCAUGGGCCGUGAUCCUCCCGCCCUGGAGCGACUGGAGGGAAAAGUGCUGGAGAGUCCCAUCCUUGGGGCUAACUGCAGAGCGGAAUCCUGUCCCUGUGAGCCUGCAGGGUGGCCGCUGGCCCUGUGCCCUAGCCCUGCUAGAUUGUAUUGGAGGCUAAAUGCCAGCACCCUGAGAUGCCUUAUCACGCUGAGUCCUCCCCACAACAGGCUUGUCAGCACUGGGAUGGUUUAUACUUUUUAAAAAUAAUGUCUCUAGACAAUAAUCAUACAUUUUUAAAAAAUUAGAAAGAAUGAAAAGCCCAGGCCCUGGAAACAUAAGGUCUAACCACAGAAUCAGAAACUCCAAAUUGGGAGAUGGCCAGACGCCACAGAAUGCGAGUGAUGGACUUGUGAGCUGUUCACGUCAAAGGCAUCGGAGCCACAGCGAGACAACCCAGAGGAUGUGAAAUCCCAGCACUUCAAUACCAAACUGUCUGCCUACCAGGUGUCAUUCAAACUGCUGUCAUUCCACCCGCCUGUGAUUCUGGACACCCAGUGAAGCAAGUUAAAGGCCACAGCAAGGCUGGAGAGAGGAGCGCUCUUUCCUCUCCCUGGUGAGGGACAGCCUCCUGCCUGGCCAGCCACCCCUUCUGGUUCCACGUGCACCCUCCCCUGGAAUUAAUGACUGGCUGAUGCUUCCGCUGGAACUCUUCAUCAAACCUUGGAAGAGAAAUCAAAGGUGUUUGAGAGGAAAGUCAUGUGUAAUACCAAGAACCACCUCCCAGCUCCUAAGUUUCAGAGAAACCAGCAGGGAAGAUAUUGAAGUCCGUGCAGUUGGACACUGGUGCCCCAAGAGCAUUGGACAAACUAUUAGAUAUCAUUGUGAACACCCCACUCCUGUCAGAGAUGGCAAAACAGGUCCCAAGAAGGAGAAGAAGGACUCGGGGUUACUCAGGGGACCAGGUGCUGUUUGCCCUGAACCAAACCCUGCUGCAGCAGGAGAGUGUGCGGGCCGGGAGCCUGCAGGCCUCCUACACCACGGAGGACCUCAUCAAGCACUACAACUGCGGAGACCUCAGCGCAGUCAUCUUCAACCACGACACAUCCCAGCUGCCCAACUUUAUCAACACCACCCUCCCGCCACACGAGCAGGUGACGGCCCAGGAGAUUGACAGCUACUUCCGCCAGGAGCUCAUCUACAAGAGGAAUGAGCGCAUGGGGAAGAGGGUCAUGGCGCUUCUACGGGAGAACGAGGACAAGAUCUGCUUCUUUGCCUUCGGAGCAGGUCACUUUCUGGGGAACAACACAGUCAUCGACAUCCUGCGGCAGGCAGGGCUGGAGGUGGACCACACACCCGCCGGGCAGGCCAUACACAGCCCUGCCCCCCAGAGCCCAGCGCCCUCUCCUGAGGGGACCUCGACGAGCCCGGCCCCAGUGACCCCAGCUGCCGCUGUCCCCGAAGCACCCUCUGUGACCCCCACCGCCCCACCAGAGGAUGAGGAUCCAGCCCUGUCCCCACACCUCCUGCUCCCCGACAGCCUCAGCCAGCUGGAGGAGUUUGGCCGGCAGAGGAAGUGGCACAAGAGGCAGAGCACACACCAGCGGCCGCGGCAGUUCAAUGACCUCUGGGUCCGCAUCGAGGACAGCACCACCGCCUCACCACCCCCGCUGCCCCUGCAGCCCACCCACAGCUCGGGGACCGCCAAGCCCCCCUUCCAGCUUUCAGACCAGCUACAACAGCAGGACCCGCCAGGGCCCGCCAGCAGCUCGGCACCCACCCUGGGCCUUCUCCCCGCCAUCGCCACCACCAUCGCUGUCUGCUUCCUGCUGCAUAGCCUUGGGCCCUCCUGACCUCGGCCACCCCAAGUGGAGAAGCCAGAGAAAUGACACAGGGGUCUUCGGCCACACCCAACUGCUCCUGCCACCACCUCCAGGGGGUGCCCAACACGUCGAGGGCAGUCCACAUGGGAUUGGCUAGACACUCUAGAGCUUUACUGUACCCAAGUUACAUCUUCUUUUUUGUAGAAGGAUCUUAAUUUCCCAUAGUGCUAUGGGGCUCUUUUGUAAAAUACGUGUCCAUAUUAAAAAAGAAAAAUGUAUUUAUUCUACCGAUAAAACUAUUCUUAUGUGGCCUGUGUUAUAACCCCCUAGCCCUAGUGCUGGCCCGGGAGGGGAACCCGGGACAUCAGUGACCUCCUGUGGACUGUGGCUCUGGACUGGCUUGCUCUUGGAUCACCGAAGCCUCCUGGGUCUGGGUUUGGCUUCUCCGACUGUGGGGCCCUCAGCAGGAGGGGCAGGCAGGCAGGCUUAGCCUUUGUGAAGCUGGAUUUGGGAGCCAGAGGUGUGAACGUUGGCCAUCCUCCCCUCUGCUGGAUGCACCCGCGGCCUGGGAAGAUAAUUUAGGAAAGAGAAUGCUGCUAUUGUGAAACCCCUGAGUGUCUAUCUGGCCCUCCAGAGCUCUUGGUAAGUGUUUUCAACCAAAGCGCUGGGGUGGGGUGGGAGGUGGGAUACUGGUGCUGAGGAAAGCAGUCCCCACCCCACAGAACAAAUGAAUAAACUGAGAUCCAGAGAGAACCAGGUGGGUAGCCCAAGGUCACACGGCAAGUGGGAGAGUGAGGACAUAAAUCCAGACCUCUCUGUUCUGGUGUCAUGAAUCCAGCUUGGGUUAAAGGAGAGGCUGUUGAAGUCCUGGCUAAAUGGAUUGAGCUGGGCCGAGGGACUGGAGUGGGCACAGGAGGGCAGUUUUAGAGACAGGGGCUUAGGCCUCACAUGAUGUUAAUAGUAAUGAGAGCUGCCAUUUUUCCAAAGCCUGCAGCGUGGCAAGCACUUUGCACACUUGCUUCACUGAUUCUUGCGCUAGUUCUGUGAGAUGUGACUAUCCCCAUUUCACAGAUGAGGAAACUGAGCCCCCCAAAGAGGCGAAGGGACUUGCUGAAGAUCCCCCAGCCAGGAUGUGGCCCCAGAUCAGUGUGAUGCAAAACAAUUCCUGCCUCCUGUUCCCUGUUCUGCCACGUUCUCUCUGCAAGGGAGCAGAUCUCACCCAAACUGGGGCCAGCACAAGCUUUCACUCCACCAAGAAACCUUUUGGCCGGCUGCUUAUGUUGACCCCUCUGGCCAAAGGGCUCUGGCAACUGCAUGUGCCAUGUGUCGCAUGUCCUGACUUGCCAGAUCUUGGAGCCCACGAGAAGCUUUCCUGCCAAAUCAAAGGCUGAGAGGUGGGCACAGCUGUGGGGCACCUGGGGAGGCACAGCAGCCAAGUGGGGAGGCAGGUGACAGGGACUCCGAGAGACUUUAGCCCCUCGGCUCCUCAAGGUGGUGGUUGAGGAGACAGAGGACCCAGGUGGGCUAACUCCCACCUGGGAGGCCUGAAACCCUAUGGGGCAGGUGCCUCAGUAAUUACAGAGUCCUGGAACCUGACAGCAGAAAGGACCCUUCACUUGAUGGAUAAUAGUAACAGUAGGAGGAAUAAUAAGGCCCACAGAGAGGAGACACUUCUCCAAGGCUGCACAGCCGGGUGGGCCUGCUGACUCCCAGCCCAGUGCACCCCAACUUUAUAGCUUCGUGGGUUUCCCUGGCAGGCUUGAUGGCAGCUAAUUGGCCCCAGUGCCAUCUUGCCCAGCUUGGCAGCUAUCUCCCUUCUGAGACGGCAAGUUCUGGGCAGCUCAUGGGAUGGUCAGGAGUCCCACGGGCAUCUUGGCAGGCAGCUGAAUUCUUUACAGCUCAGCCCUGAUGGACGUGUUUGAGCUUGAGACCUGGCAGGAGACUGGAGCUCUGCCUUAGAGGGCCCAGCCAGCCCUGUGGGCACCAUGCUCUAAACUGAACUUGACCUCAAUCCAGGCUGGAGUUGGUUUAUCCUUGGCAAAAAUGUGACUUCCUAUUUCUGAGCGGGAAGGGGCUUAGCUGACUUAUAAAGCAGGCUCAGAAGUUGGACAUCAAACGGAUCGUGCAGUGCACUAUUUGGAUGAGAUAAGUGUAAAGGAAUUAGAAGCACACAGGCCAGAUUCCUCUCUGUUUGGGGCAGAGUAUGGCGUGAGACGUAUUGAGAUGGAGCUUGAGGUUAAUUAAAGAUGAAGCAUUUGGGUAAACAGUCCAGGCACCUGACCGUGUGCCCAGAUCUGUGCCAGGCACUGAGCCAAGAAGGUAAAUUAAUGCAGCUUGUAAUUACUGAGCACAUGCAAUGCCAGGCUCUGUAUUAGAGCUGAAUCUAACCACUCUCCUUGGCCCAGAGGAACUCAUUAUCAAGAUGGGACAAGCAGUGCAAUGCUAGAUUACGUCGUCCUGGCCCCUAACUUCAGGAAGAUUCAGCCUUAGUCUUUCCCAGAUCCCUCCUCUGGGCAUAUUAGGGGAUCCUAAACUCUCCCUUACCCUAAUUCAAGUGUUUAAAGAAAGAUGGCUAGACUAACCGAUGGAGUAGACAUGUACCUACAGGAGAGCAAGAGCCAAUGUGGUCAGACAUCUGUUGCCAAAGUUCACUGAUCUCUGAGGACCACCAGCUGGCCAGGGUCUGAAAUGAACUCAACUUGCUGACUUAUGACCCAAAAGACUUGAGGCACAUAUGCAGGAAUCUGCAUGUCUGGGGCACUUGAAUUCUCUCAUCCUGGGCCAGAGAACCACCAUUCCAUAAGCAGCAACCCACACCUUUGACACGAUCUAUCCACCACUAACUGACAUUUCUUCCAGAAACGUUCUUUGUGCCCAGCCUCAUAAAAUGCUCCUGUUGCUCUGAGAAAUUUGUGUGCACUUCUUAGACUUUUCUGUUUGACUGUGAGGCAGGCAGGAAAGAUGAAAGGUCUGAGACCCAGCAGGUAAAGUGAUCUGCUUAAGGUCGGGCAGCAUGUUAUUGUGGCCCUGGGUCCUCUACCUCUCACGAAAGCUGACUGUGUGAUGAAGGGCUCUCUGGGGCAUGUUGGAAUGGCCAUGUCCCCAGGUCUUCCUCCAGUGGUGGGUCUGAUGCACCAGCAGCCAGAUGAAGACAGGGAGAGCCCUGUCAUCCACAGUGGAGGGAGAAGAAUCAGGCUGCCAGGGAGCUGCAAAGGGCUGCUGAGGAUGCCUCCAGUCCUGAGAGUCAAAGAUCUGGGAUCUAGGAAGCAUGGAACCUUGUGCUGGUUAUGAACAAAUUUGUCCUUGCAUUGAAAGACCCUAAGCAUAUUUUCUUCAUGCUAAAUAAUGUGUUAUCUACAACUUCCUGGCCUCGGCUAGACCUGGACAAGCCUAGGUGCUCAGGCCCCUUGUCCCACUUGCCUAAUCUCCAGCCCAGGGCCAUUGUCACAGUGGAUCCCAAAGAGGAGGGAAAGUCCUUCUACCAAAAGGAAAGUCUAUUGAAAAUGCUGUGAAGGACAAGAGAAGUUCUCCAGGGAAUUGCAGCUUUGAUGGCAUCCUGUGUGGCAGACAGCAGAAUUGGGGCUGGUGAUAGUUUUUCAGUGACUGUGAGAUAAGAACCAGAGUCCUCAGCCUCACCCUGAAGUGUCCGCUAGACCCUUCGUGACCCAACCCUGCUGACCAGCCACGUCUCUCAUGUCUCUUACCCUGUGCCUGGCCAGCGUGAUGUGCAGUCAUCUCUAGAAUAGACAGGAUGUUUCACACAUGCUGCUCCCUACCCCUGGAAACUCCCUUCUCUCCCCUGUAACUGCUCAUCCAUUGAGGAUCAACACAGAUAGCACUUCCUCCAGGAAGCCCCCUCCCAUUCCUUUGUGCUUUCUUAGCAUCUAUCACAAUACCCACUGCCCAGUGUUGUGACUAUCUAGUGUGUAUCUGCUCCUCUCGGACUGUGAGCAGCUUAAUGGCAGGGGUCAUGUAAAUUUGUUUUUGUACCCUCAUCUGACACAAAGGUGGUGCUCAACAGAUGUGUAGAGAGAGAAAGGAAGGGAAGGAAGCUGAAGGAAGGGGAGGAAGAAAGGAAUGAAGGCAGAAAAGAAGGAGAGAGGCAGACCUUAGUUCCACCAGUGGCAUAAUUUCCACCAAGCCAAAGCUGUCUGGGGAUGGCCCGGAGCCCCCAAGGGUGGCAGGUUUCCCAUCGGGAGAGGUGUUUGAGCAGGGGCAGUGUGCCCACUGGCUGAAGAAGUGGUAGGAGAGUUGACAUCUUGCCAAGGGCCUGGUGUAGAUGACAUUGAGGGUCCCUCCUGGCUCUGCAAUGAUCAAGUUCUAUGAACAUUGUUAUUUUUCCAGAAAUUCAUCUGAGCAGCCAAAAAAAAUCACCCCGCUGGCUGUCUAAACCAGUAAGGUUCAGGAAUAAGUCCAGCCUCCCCACUCCACCCACAACCACCACCACCCCUCACAGCGCCCCCUUCAAUGACCCAGCUGGGCUUGACUGCUGCCUUUGGGUGGGGGAACUUCUGAAAGGUGGAGGAGGAGUGAACUGGAACCCAGGCCUGCAGCCCAGCCCAGAGCUCCUUCCCGCUCUGCCCCACUCCCUGACCCCAGGGGAGGAAAGGGUUCACGAGAACUGAUUGACCCCCUACUUGGCUCUUUCCAGGGAGCAUCGGCUAUCCUCACCCUUUCUCCAAGUGGGAGCUGGGCUCUUCCUUUCCGGAGAUACUCUGGAUACUCCUUCACUUUGCUGGAUGACCUUGGGCAAGUUCCUGUCCCUCUCUGAGCCUUCACUUCCUCAUCUGUCAAAUGAAGACCUUGAUUCCUGCCUGGGCAGUUCUAGGGCUGGAGGGCAGGGGUGACAUGGACAAUCUUGGGCCUCCAUGGAGAUGAGGUGCUUGGCUUUCUUCCCAGGACCCACAGGCUGCCAUGGGAUUGAAAGCAUGUGGAGGUGGGAAAGGUGACAGAGUAGCAUGCCUCCAAGGCCCCCUUCAUCCCAGUCCUGCUGUGGGGAAAGUGGGCUUUGAACGGGAUCCAAGUCUAAGAUGUUUCCGGUGAGCUGCCAGGGACAAAGGGCUCUCAGACAUCUUGGGUCCCCAGUGGCUGGGGUGGGCAGGGGCUGAUUCAGCCAAAGGAGGCUCUAGCCCAGAACAGAGGAAGCCAGAGCCCCUGCCCCAUUCUUGAGCCUCACAGAGCUUGUCCCCGAGUUGAUUCACUGUGCAACACAGGCUUCAGAUUCAUGUAUUUGAAAGGUAUUCAUGAUGUUGUUCUCUUAUCACCUCUGCCCCUCACCUCUGUGAAUUAUCAUGAAGAGUCCUUUAAGAGUAUAAAUAGAAGACAAAGAAAGAUGCUAUUAAUGUUAUUUUGCCAAAAAUAUUUUUGUAGCAUAAUAUAUUAAUAAAAGAUAUUAUGAAUUCAA